AAACAAAUAGUGUCUAAUCUUCUUUGAUUGAACGGUAAAUAUGAGAGAUACUGCAUAUAAGAACAUUAUUAUGUUGUAAAAAACUUUGUUGGUUUGAUAUCUUUUAUUGGUUUUUCUUGAGUUAGACAAAUAAAAUAAGGUAAUGUGGCAGUAUAUAUAUUGCAAAGUAGAAGUAAAAGUCAUCUAGUCACCUCCCAGGGGUGUGGGAAGUAUCAUGAUAUCUGAACUUACUUUUAGAAAAAAAAUGUAUAUGCAUGUAGAGAAAAAGAAGGCAGAUGUCAAAAAUUAGGGAAUUGAGGUGAAGGGUAUUUGGGAGUUCCUUGUACUAUUAUUUCAACAACUUUUUUAGGUUGAUUUUUUUCAAAAACCCGUCUCUCGUAAUCCUACCCUCAGAAAGAAUUAGAUGUGGAUCCUGAGAGGUCACAGGUGUGCUAGGCAUUUUGCAUACAUUUUAAAUUUAGUUCUCAGCUCUCGAGGAGGAAACAAAGGUGAUGGCAGGUGACCAGGGUCACACAACUUGGCUGAGUAGUGGAACCAGAAUUUGGAUGUGUUACUUCAGACCAGACCCUAGGGGAAAAAAAAAGAAUUUGGACUUAGACCUCUGACCCCAAUGCCUUUAUUCCUUUAUGGCCUUGUGUAUCUCAAAUAGCAAACCUUUCCCAUGGGAAGGAAUGACUGGCUUCCUCUGUCAUCCUCUAGGUCCUUGAUACUUUAUGAGCCUGUGCUUAGUGAAAGCAGAUGGGAGAUAGCCCAGGCGGGGCUGCCAUCCUGGGACUUGCAGGAAAACUAAGAAGGGAACUGAAGCUGCCCACCUUCCGAGCCCACUCCCCACUCCUGAAGAGCCGCCGGUUCUUCGUGGACAUCCUGACCCUGCUGAGCAGCCACUGCCAGCUCUGCCCUGCAGCCCGGCACCUGGCCGUCUACCUGCUGGACCACUUCAUGGAUCGCUACAACGUCACCACCUCCAAGCAGCUCUACACCGUGGCCGUCUCCUGCCUCCUGCUUGCAAACGGAGUUUCGCUCUUAUCGCCCAGGCUGAAGUGCAGUGGCAUGAUCUCAGCUCAUUGCAACCUCCACCUCCCAGGUUCAAGCAAUUCUCCUGCUUCAGCGCCCCACCCCCCACCCACACCGCCCCAAGUAGCUGAGACUACAGGUAAGUUCGAGGAUCGGGAAGACCACGUCCCCAAGUUGGAGCAAAUAAACAGCACGAGGAUCCUGAGCAGCCAGAACUUCACCCUCACCAAGAAGGAGCUGCUGAGCACAGAGCUGCUGCUCCUGGAGGCCUUCAGCUGGAACCUCUGCCUGCCCACGCCUGCCCACUUCCUGGACUACUACCUCUUGGCCUCCGUCAGCCAGAAGGACCACCACUGCCACACCUGGCCCACCACCUGCCCCCGCAAGACCAAAGAGUGCCUCAAGGAGUAUGCCCAUUACUUCCUAGAGGUCACCCUGCAAGAUCACAUAUUCUACAAAUUCCAGCCUUCUGUGGUCGCUGCGGCCUGUGUUGGGGCCUCCAGGAUUUGCCUGCAGCUUUCUCCCUACUGGACCAGAGACCUGCAGAGGAUCUCAAGCUAUUCCCUGGAGCACCUCAGCACGUGUAUUGAAAUCCUGCUGGUAGUGUAUGACAACGUCCUCAAGGAUGCCGUAGCCGUCAAGAGCCAGGCCUUGGCAAUGGUGCCCGGCACACCCCCCACCCCCACUCAAGUGCUGUUCCAGCCACCAGCCUACCCGGCCCUCGGCCAGCCAGCGACCACCCUGGCACAGUUCCAGACCCCCGUGCAGGACCUAUGCUUGGCCUAUCGGGACUCCUUGCAGGCCCACCGUUCAGGGAGCCUGCUCUCGGGGAGUACAGGCUCAUCCCUCCACACCCCGUACCAACCGCUGCAGCCCUUGGAUAUGUGUCCCGUGCCCGUCCCUGCAUCCCUUAGCAUGCAUAUGGCCAUUGCAGCUGAGCCCAGGCACUGCCUCGCCACCACCUAUGGAAGCAGCUACUUCAGUGGGAGCCACAUGUUCCCCACCGGCUGCUUUGACAGAUAGGCCACCUCCAGACCUCACGAGGAAGCCUUGGAGAUGUGGGCAGAGGAAGAGGACACUGAAGAGGAGAGCUCAGCCAAGUGAGGCAGCAGGAGGCCAUCCCUGAAGAGCCUUGGAACGUGGAGGGUCUGUGCUCCUUUUAAAUAAAACUGACCCAGAGCAAAACAUUCAAUAACAUACCUCACCCGAGAGCAUUCCUCUGAGAAACGUCUGCCACGUGUGGCUAGGGUACAAAAGGAUGGCUUGGUGGCCGUCCCCCCACACAGGGGCCCAGUGAAUCGAGAAAGACUUGAUAAGAGGCCAGGAGAGUGGGAACUGGACACAGACCACUGAUCUCAAGCAUGUCCAGUUUUUAGCAUUAAAGACUUUUCUAUUCUUUGCUGAUGGCAGCUACACCGCUGAAAAAGGAGGGGCAGCCUGGCGUGUUCUCAGGACCCCCGGAGGAUCCCAUAUUGGGUGCUUUUCUUUCCCUGGCUCUAUGCAGAGGGGCCUGAGUUGGUGUGUAUGCCUGAGUGUUUGCCUUGCGAGGCACAGUGGGUGGCUGUCUUGCCUUUGUUUUCGAACCUAAAACCAUUUUCAGCCUUUUAGAUAUGUCAUGUGCUGCUGCUUCCCGAAGUGGUCUUGCUUUCUGUUUCGUAAGAUGUCUUGUUUACACACUGUAUCAGGGAUUUGGUGAUACUUGAAAAUUCCUUUGGAGAAAAAAACAAAUUUAAUUGCCACACUGCCUGUCCCACAUGAGGGCUGUUAAUUUGGAACCCAAGUUUGAACCCAACUUGUGAUGGACCCGCAGGUAACCACAGAGCUUCCUUUUUGAAGGCAUAUGGUUGGAGAGAACCAUUUUCCCAGCUCUCGGUUCCGGAAGAUUCCACGUCUUGGAGGCUGUGUUCACCACUAGAACUUUAAUAACUACCCAGGGAGGGAGAAGCUCGUUGAAAGGAAGACAAAGAUUUAAACAGUUCCCACCUCUCUCCACCACAUACUUACAGGGCAUGAGUUUAACCCAGUCUAGGCUUUGAGUGUGGCUGAUAGCGAAGGAUAGCAAUGUGGAAAAUUUGCUUAGUCCCACCUGUAUUUGGGGAGUGGGAUGUACAUGGGCGUUUGAUACCACCAUUGAUAGGCAAGCGACUGGUUGGAUCAAAAGCCAGUAUUUAGGGAUCUGCAGCGAGAGGGCCCUCAGGAAGACUCUUGUAACCAUGUGCAAUAUGUUUUUAUUCUGACUCGCAGCUUGUGCUCAGCAUGUUCUUUGGUUUAGUUUGGGGUUGGGGGACACAUUGUUCACCCAGCAGAACUGGGAGGUGCAAAGGACCGUGGAAGCAAUUUUUGUUUUGUUUGAGGAAUACCUGUCUUGGAUUCCUUAGCCCCUUGCCAGUCCUGGAGACUGUGGCAGGGGCCGCCAGGAAGGCAGCUGUCUGCUGCUGAGUCAGAUCGGAAGGUGGUGAAUCUUUCCAGAGCAGCUGAAAAUCUCAGCAUGGAGACAGUAAGAAAAGAGACGGGGUGUGGAUAAGACUCUGCCACCGUGUCACACUAGCAUAGGAGGCUGCACGUUCAUUUGUUGUUGUUUUUUUUUCCUUUGCCAACCUCCGUUCUAUUUAUGUGCAAGCAGUUUGGAUUCAAGUUCUUGUAUCUGUCUGUUCUGGGACCUGGGGAUUGUGAGGGUUCCCUCACAGCCAGCACGACCCCCAGAAAGAGGCGUCCCACAAUAAACACGUCACCUGCUCUUGAUCUCUCACCUCUUGUCCUAGGCAUCCCCUCUUGGGCCGGCCCCUCCUUCCCUCUCUCAAAUCAGCCCUGGUGAGCAUCUCCCUAUGGUAGAGGGUGGAAUAUUGGGGGCAGCAGCAAGACCUCGGGAGCUGAGUCCUGCCCUCUGAGUAGGAGCUGGGCCUCCCUGGGCACACAGAGGCCAGCGGAGGGGUGUAUAAGGCUUGACACCCCAGCUCCAUCACCGUCUCAGGGUUUUUCCAAAGAAACCAGUAGGAUAUAUAUGGAGAGAGAUUUAUUUUAAGGAAUUGGCUCAUGUGAUUGCAGAGGCUGUGGUCUAAAAUUUGUGGGGCAUGUCAGCAGGCUGGAAAUUCAGGUAAGAGCUGAUGUUGCAGUAGAGUUCAAAAUCUGUAGGGCAGGCCCACAGGCUGGAAACUCAGGCAUGAUUUCUGUGUUAGCAGUCGUGAGGCAAAAUUUAUUCUCCAGGAAACCUCAAUCUUUGCUCUUACGACCUUUUACCAGUUGGAUGAGGCCCACCCACAUUAUGGAGGCUUUUCUUAAAGUCAACUGAUUGUAAAUGUUAAUCACAUCUAAAAAUACCUUGACAGCAACAUCUAGACUAGUACCUAGCCACACAACAGGCACUGUAGCCUAGCCAAGCUGCCACAUAAACUUAAUGAUCACACCACUUACCAGCUGUUGGAAGGCAGUUGACCCAACCUCUCUCUGAGCCUCCAUCUUGUCACCUGUUAAAAUGGGAGUGAUAACACCUUGCCUCAUAGGGUUCUUAAGAGGAUUAAAUAACAUAAUGUACAUCAAGGCCAGUACCUCCAAAAAAGGAGAUAAUUAUUAUAUUUCUUCAAGCAUAAGAUCAGCUUUUUGUAAGAUGCACUAUUAUUUUAUGCACUAAUAAGACUUUUUAGAAAACUAAAUCAUGAGGCAGUUUGCAAGAUACCAUUGAUUAUAUGUUGCAUUCUGAUUUCAGAAGCGUUACAUGUCAAAAUAUGUAUAUGUAGAAUUGAUGAGAUAUAGCAUCAGCUGUUAUGAAAAAUGUCAGAUUCGUACUCCUCCUUGAAGGGAGUCUCACUCAAGACUUCUGUCUUGCCCUCUACCUACCCAGCUUCCAGCAGGAGAACCACCCCAGAGAGCCGGUGUCACUGUGGGGCUGAGACAUUUGCUAAGUGCAGAUGCCUUUGAUUAGACAAUUAGGGGAGGAAUGGGAAGAUGAGCUCAGGGCCUGAGGCUGCAGCCCAGACCCAGGAGUGUGUUUGACACCGCCAAGGGCGGGGCUGAGGGCAGUGCUCACCACCCGCUGUGUGCAAGGCUAGGUGAGGCAGGAAGCUCUAAGUUUUGGGGAUUCAGAGACAAGGCAAGUCUUGGGUUGACCAAGAGCACCCACCUCACUUUGGACAAAUCCCUCCCUCUUUGGGCUUCCAUUUCUCCAUCUGUUACUAUGGAGAUGGUCAAGUUGGUGGAUGGUUCUAAGCUCUUGGGGCGGGGGGAGACUGUGCCACAGAGGCUGUGACCUCUGUGGCCUUCAGCCAGAGGGAUCCACUUGUAUUUCUUCCACCCUUGGGCACUCCCAUGUAAGAUUGUGUUAAUUCCCAUGCUGGAGGACAGCUAUGAAAGCUUUAAAAAGCACAAAGAUAGUCUUAAAGUUCCUCCCAGGGCUGGCAUCAGGUUAAAUUCAGAGGUUUUCAAGCCUGAGCAAGCUGCAGAAUGACCUGGAGCCUUCUCUAGGAGGGGUGGGGACCUGGAAUCUGCACUUUAGCCAGCUUCUUGGUCAUUCAGGCAUAUGAUUUCUUUGUUUGUUUUUUAUAUUUCAGUUGUAUUUUUAUAACUCCCCAGUUUAGUUUGAUUUUUUAAAUUUUUAUUUUAUUUAUUUAUUUAUUUAUUUAUUUAUUUAUUUAUUUAUUUUUUGAAACAGGGUCUCACUCUGUGGCCCAGGCUAGAGUGCAGUGGCACAGUCACGGCUCACUGCAGCUUCAACCUUCUGGGCUCAAGUGAUCCUCCCACCUCAGCCUCCUGAGUAGCUGGGACUACAGGCACCUGUCACCAUACCCAGCUAAUUUUGGUAUUUUUUGUAGAGAUGAGGUUUCACCAUGUUGUCCAGGCUGGUCUCAGACUCCUGAGCUCAAGCAAUCUGACUGCCUCGGCCUCCCAAAGUGCUGAGAUUACAGGUAUAAGCCACUACGCCUGGUCCAGCUUGUUUUGAAAAGUAUUUUCUGACGUCUAUAUGAAUUUAACAGAAUUAUCUCAAAGUACACAGAAAUUACCUGUAUUUGCCAGUAAAUAUGAGAUGCUGAUGAAAGAAUACUCAAUAUACCAAUAUUUAAGCAUGUCAACAUAAUAGAACUUUUUCCACCUUUUAAAAUUAUUUUUCCCACCUAACCCAAUUUAUAUUUGACAUUUGGGUUACAUGUGCAUAUAGAAACAGACCUAUUCCACAACUGACCAUAGAUAAACUAGCAUGCAAGUGUCCUUUCUGGAUGUAAUUAAGUUUCAGAGGCAGCAUGGUUCAAAUGGGAGCAAAUGAGCUGACCUCCUCAUGAAAUACACUAGGCAAAAAAUCAAGAAGUAUUAAAGUUGCUAAAGACUGA